GCGACAGAGCGAGACUCCGUCUCAAAAAAAAAACAAAACUAGGGUUAGAACUCACAAGAGCUACAACUUACUAGAGCUGGAACUCACUAGAGCUAUAACUCAUUAGGGCUAGAACUCACUAGAGUUAGAACUCACUAGAGCUAGAUCUCACUAGGGCCAGGACUCACUAGAGUUAGAACUCACUAGGGCUAGGACUAAGUUCCUGGAGCUCCUUCAAGUUGCUUCAAGUUCCAGAUGCUUGAGAUGCUCAGGCUUUGUUUAAGGGCGGCUUUCCUUUUCUUCCCAGAGUCCCGAGGGACAGAGAAGCUGCCUUUCACCCUGUCUGGCCACUUUCCCCGAGGGGCAUCCUUUGGAGGGUCUGGACUUUGCAGCCUUGCCUCCCGCGCCUUUGGGCAUGGCACCCUCCUGGACAGCGCUGAGGUCUCCUCACACACUCAUGAAUCCACAGAGGACGGCGCCGCUGAGGCUGCUGCACAGCAGCGAGGGCCAACUUGCUGUAGAAUCUUCCGGAAGCCAGAGCCCAAAACAGAUGCUUUGCUUCUCUUCGUCCACCUCUUAUCCGUUUCCCAAAUCUCCUGCGGGUCAGGGAUAGAAAACUCCGGGAGGAAGCCUGGCGGGGGUUUGCUGCCUUGGACGACCCCCUGGCCGGGCUUCUGGACAUGCUGGAGAGCUGCCGGGGCCAGCGGGGAGAGGGCCCCUCCCUGGCGGCCUGGAUCUCCCACCAGCUGCAGUGCUGGCUACAGGCACAGCCAUGCCCGAGCCUGGCCCAGCCUGAGGCUGAAGCAGCUGCAGGCCCGAGCGGUCAAAGUCCUCACUGAGAGCCCCCCCAGCCUUGCGGCACCACUGGCCAGCAUCUUCCAGCUGCAGGAUGCAGACAGGAGCUGCCUGCUGGCACACGUCCACCGCCUCCACCACGAGGGCAGGUUCAGAGAAGCAGCCACGCUGGGCGCGACGUUGAAGCUGCAGUCGGAGCUUGGCGUUGAAAAGAUGAGCAUCCCACUGCUCCUCCAGGACAAGGUGGCCCUCGUGGAGCGCUAUGUGGCCGGCUUCCCGGACCUCCAGAGGAGGCUGCUGGUCCUCAUGGAUUCCUGGUGCCAGCCCGGCUUUGACAUCAAGGACGUUGCCAGACAAAAAUUUCAAGAGAAUAAGAGGGGAGACGGGAGCUGGAACCCGGAAGACAGAUGUCCAGGCAGCGACUGUCCUCGGAGGCCUGAGAGUGCUGAACCUGCAAAUGCAAGGAGCCAGUUGGCUUCGGAGCCCCCGGGAGGCACAGGAAGUGGAGGCCCAGAUUCCUCCAAGAAGCUGGGCUGGAAACAGGGUCUCCAGGGGGUCUUUGUGAGCGGCACGGUGUUCUGGCCACAGCUGAGGACAGGGCUGGGGCUCCGUGCUGAAACCAGGAGGACACAGGUUUCCAGAUGUGAGGCCACGGGAGCCCCCACAGGAGCCGGACUUAACAGACGGUACCCUGAGGUGACCUCCUUGAGCCUGGAGAAGCUGAGUCCGAAGGCGCUGAGCAGGCAGGUCUUGCGUCUGCAGGAGCGGUACGGCGUAGCCCCAGCGCUGUGUCCCAACGCGGCCAUUCAGCAGCGCCUGGCGGCCCUGCGGCACCUGUGCCACAAGCGGUUUGUGGAGGUUCGUGAGCAGGAGGGGGUCCUGGGGGCAGCCAGCCGCGGCCUGAGCCACAGAGUUUGGCCUGGGAUACUCACUGCGCACUGCAGGGUGCACAGACAUAUCAAAAGAGCCUGUCACAGGAGAACUGGACCGACCAUGUGCAGUGACCCAGUCACGGCCGCCCAGUGUGCCAUGGAACUCUUGCUGCCCGAGGAGCGGCUGCCGGCUGCGGUGGCUGUGGAACUCCGCCGGUUCAGGCUCCAGGGGAGGGCGACUGAGGCUGACUCGAGGCUGGAGGUGAAGGACAUGAAGGACCGUUACUACCAGCUGCCCAUCCCCAGGGAGAACGUCCACCUCCUGGCCUCGUGGGAAGACCUGACCAGACACGAGGGUGCACUCCUGCAGUGCCACCAAGUGGUUGGUGUAGACGUGGAGUGGACACCUGUGUUUGUUGCUGGGGGCCGGCCUCGGCCGUCACUCCUGCAGGUGGCCGUGGAGGGCCACGUGUUCCUUCUGGACGUCCUGGCACUCUCGCAGCCACCAACAGGGCAGGGAGCCCAGGCCUUUUCCCGGCUGGUGGCCCAGCUCCUCUCGGACCCCUCUAUCACCAAGCUGGGCUACGGGAUGGUGGGGGACCUGCAAAAACUGGGCACGUCCUGCCCCGCCCUGGCCCAUGUGGAGAAGCAGAUUCUGGGCGGCAUGGACCUGCUGCUGGUGCACAGACAGCAGAUGCGGGUGGCGAGCGUGCCAGCCCCAGCCGUGGACAGGGCCAGGGAGCUGAGGGGCCUGAGCCUCCUGGUGCAGCAGGUGCUGGGCACAGCCCUGGACAAGACGCAGCAGCUGUCCAACUGGGACCGGAGGCCGCUCUGCGAGGAGCAGGUCAUCUACGCAGCUGCCGACGCCUACUGCCUGCUGGAGGUGCACCAAGCCCUGUGCAGAGAGCCCGCCCGCUUCCACCUGUCGGAGGACCUGGCUGGGAGCCGGAGGCCCAGGCACAGAGAGAGACCAGGGGCACGGAAGCCACCCGGCCUGCAGAAAGCGUCAGCACCGGCCGCACCCAGGCAGGUCCCUGUGGCUGUGGCUGUGUCUGAGGGCGCUGCCCCUCAGAUUCCGGCCAGGGCCUUCCGUGUGGUGUGUGACAACAUGCUGCAGGGGCUGGCACGGAGCCUCCGCUGUCUCGGUGUGGAUGCACGCAUGCUGGGCAAUGGUGAAGACCACCGCAGGGCGGCCGAGGUUGCCAGGCAGGAGGGGAGGAUCAUUCUGACGUCGGGGCAGCCAUUCCACAAGCUCCGGGCCCAGGUCGGGGCUGGGCGCUGCCUCUCGGUCGACUGCUCCCUGAAGGCCCAGCAGCAGGCCAAGGCUGUGCUCAAGCAUUUCAACGUGCGUGUCACCCACGCAGACAUCUUCAGCCGCUGCCAGACCCAGAGCUUCGAGGAGCGAGCAGAGGGCUGGGGUAUGGGGCACCCGGAGAAGCCCCGCCUGGGCCUCAGCACCCCCUCUGGCCCCCAGGCCUGUAACUGUGACCAGUACCUAAAGGUCUCCAGGGACAUGAUGAAGCAGCUCAUGUGGCUCAGCAGUCACCAGGAGGGGCCCAGGAGCUCAGGUGACGAGGCCACCCAGAGCCAGGCGGUGCAGGAGCCAGGCCCAGCCCCAGACGCAGCCCCUGAGGGCUGCACCUAUGACCGCCCCUGCCGCUGGCUGCAGAUGGCUGACCUGCGGGCGGAGACACCGGACAUGCUGGCCGACGGCACCCGGCUGCAGCUGGCAGGGGUCCCGGUGGGUGUGCUGAGGACACCUGGGCUGCGGUGCUUCUACUGCUGCACGGGCUGUGGAAAGGUCUUCUGGGACGGCUCCCACCUGGGUCGUGUUGCCACCCACUUCCGAGACAUGCUGGAGAGCGCCCCCAGCCCCUGCGAGCCGAGCCCAGCCCCCAGCCCGGCCAGCAGUCCCUUCUGAGGACAGCCAGACAAUAAACAUGGAAAGUGCCCGACUGCUGGGCCCAUGGCCGUG